CCUCACCUCGCCCGGACGGCGGCCUUCGGAAGUCGGCGCCUGCCAGCUACCCGCCGCCUCCUCAGCAAUCUUAGCCGACCGGGAGGGCUCGGCCCAGGUCACCGGCAGCCCAGGCGCAGGCGGGAGCAUCCAAUCAACUUCGAGAGCGUAGGCCCCACCUAUCGUGGGUCGAGUUGCUUGGCGGUCGUGGUUCCGGAGGUUCCUCGGGAUGUCGGUGGCCUUCGUACCGGACUGGCUGAGGGGCAAGGCGGAAGUCAAUCAAGAGACUAUCCAGCGGCUCCUUGAGGAGAAUGACCAGCUGAUCCGCUGUAUUGUGGAGUAUCAGAACAAGGGCCGCGGGAACGAGUGCGUGCAGUACCAGCAUGUGUUACAUAGAAAUCUCAUUUAUUUGGCUACCAUUGCAGAUGCCAGUCCAACCAGCACUUCAAAAGCAAUGGAAUAAUCUUUCAAAAGCAAUAGAAUAAUCUUCCAUUUGGCUGUCGUGAGGAGUAAUUGAAUGUAAUCCAUCUCUUACAAAAUGGAGACAGGGUCUUUACCAACUCAACUGGUUAAAACAUGAAUGAAACCUCUGUGGCUCUUUCGAAACGUGAAAAUGUGAAGAAAGCUACUAACUUAGCUGUAUUCUCAUGUAAAUAUUUUUUAAAUAAUUAAGCAAAUCCCUCAAUAAGUUGAGCCCAGGUGUCCUCUUUCCUGAACUUGGAGCAUGUUUGGAUAACAAAGACAUCACUGGGAUGUUCAAGUCUACUUUUUAGUUUCAACCUGAAGAGGAAACUCAGUAGGUGUUGGGCAGGAAUUGGUGAGAUUCCUGACUUGAUACCUUGCUAAAUGGACAUGUAACUGUGUGCUCCUUCCUAUCAGUUUGUAAAUGUGGUCCCCCUGACUGCUGUUUUCAGAUUGCUUUGAAAUAAAGCUUAUUUUUCUAUAAAAUACUGAUGUGGAGGUAUAGAAGUUUUCAUGUAAUAAGUAUUCCAUUUGGUUUUCAAGAAUAACUGUGAGGACUUAACCAUAAAGUAUAUAAAAACAAUACUAUUAUCAUUGCCAACAAAAUGAAUAGUGAUUUCUAAUUAUUAUCUAAUAUCAUCUGAUAAUAGAUGAUGUUUAAUUUUCUUCAGUUAUCAGAUAGUCUUUUUGUUGAUUUGUCUGAACCAGAAUCCAAAUAAGAUUCACAUGUUGUAUUUUGUUGAUGUUCCUUUAAGUCACUUAAAGAAUACUUAAUAGUUCCUUUUUUUCUUUAUUUGUUGAAAUAACUAGGUGUUUACCCUAGAAUUCUCUCGUGUUCUACAUACAGUUGUAUCUCUGUAGUGUUGUUAAUUAUGUGCCACUAUCAUCCACUUUUCCUGUAAACUAGUAGAUCUAGAGGCUCAUGCAGACUCAUGUUCUAAUAUUUUUAGCAGGAAUAUAUUAGAAGGUGAUAAGUACUUGCUUUUGCAUCACAUAAGGAGUGACCUGACUUUUAAGUUCCCAACCAGCCUUUCACUUAAAUUAUGAUCCACCCAGCUUUGAUGUGGUAAUUCAUUAGGGAUUACAUAAUGAGGAUUUUCUAAUUUAUCAUUCUUUCUGACUUUAUUAGCUGUAUUCUAUAAAAAACUUUCACUCUUGGAGAUUUAUCUGAAAGAUGAGGCAAAGGGAUUCUUGUAAGUAUAUCCAAAAUUAGAAGCCCAGGUCCCUGCUCCUUUUUUUGGAGUCAAGGGUUGCAACCUAGGGCAACUGUAAAAUACAUGUAAAUAGUGAAGAGAUAACUCAUUUUGAAUCCCAGCUCUAUCCCUUAACCUCUGAAAGCUCUGUUUCCUCACCUCUAAAGUGAGGAUAAUGAAAAUAGCAUCUGCCUCCUGAGGUUGUGAGACUGAGAUAACGUGGUUGAGAACUGGGCACAUGUUAAUCUAUGUUAGCACUAAUGUGCUGAGGGCUCUGGCUCUUUCUUUUUUCUUUUUCUUCUUUUUUUUGGUUUUGUUUUGUUUUGUUUUUGUUUUUGUUUUUUUUUGAGACGGAAUCUCGCUCUGUCGGAGUGCAGUGGUGCAAUUUUGGCUCACUGCAACCUCUACCUCCUGGGUUCAAGUGAUUCUCCUGCCUCAGCCUCCCAAGUAGCUGGGAUUACAGGCAUGUGGCACCAUGCCUGGCUAAUUUUGGUAUUUUUAGUAGAGACGGGGUUUCUCCAUGUUGGUCAGGCUGGUCUCGUACUCACGACCUCAGGUGAUCCACCUGCCUCAGCCUCCUAGAGUGCUGGGAUUACAGGCGUAAGCCACCGCGCCCAGCCGAUCAUUUCUGUUUUCUAGAAAAUUAUUUUGUCUGUUUCCCCACUAGCAUUCCUGAUGGUUUUCCAGAGUCCUAUCCCCUGAAGUUCUAAUUGCUGGCAUAAUCACACUCUAAAAGGCUGAACCCCAGAAUCAUUACCUGAAAAUUCGUACUACCAGUGGUUCUUCUUCAUGAUAAAUCAUGGACAAAUUAAGCCUGAGUUUGUAAACUCUUUGGAUACCAACUUUCUACCACUCUUGGAAGAGAUGGAGGAGGUGUCAGUCAUUUUGGUUGAUACUAGCCCUAGGCCUGCCUUGUCCCAGGAGUUUCUUCACCUUAAUCACAGACCAAAUUGCAUACUUUUAUCUUCGAAUCAUCUAAAAUAUAAUUUCAAAUCACAAGACAGAAUAAAAUAAUCUUUGAGAGAGGCAGAACCUUAGAAAGGAGAUAUUUUAUCUCAUUUAUUUUACAGAUGAAGAAAGUAAACUUCAGAGAGAUCAAAGUGAUUUGUCUCAGGUCACAUAACCAGUGGCAGAAAGAAGAGAAUUGCUGGAAUGUCAAGAUAAGAAUGAAUUCUAGGUUUAAAGUUGUUUAAGUAUAUCCCAAAUUAAAUAUUUCAUUCCUGAGCUCUAAAA